AAAGUGAAUGGCGAAGGACUGAAGGGAUCCCCCCUUCGGGUCCCCGGCCGCCCUGUUCACCCUCGUUCAUCCUCCUUUCCGAAGCUCGCUCUCGAAGGCAGGAGCGACCGGCGCCUUUGGCUGAGGAGGAGGAGAAGGAGGAAUCGCGCCAGGCGGAGCGUCAGGUCCCGUUUUCCUCUCCGGCGUCUCCAAUACAAAGAUUACGGUGCAGAAGGAAAUUGCACUCGUCUCCUCCGCGCCCCCGGUACCCAACACAAUGCACCAGCCGCCUGAGUCCACCGCCGCGGCCGCCGCCGCUGCAGACAUUAGCGCUAGGAAGAUGGCGCACCCGGCAAUGUUCCCUCGAAGGGGCAGCGGUAGUGGCAGCGCCUCUGCUCUCAAUGCAGCAGGUACCGGCGUCGGUAGUAAUGCCACAUCUUCCGAGGAUUUUCCGCCUCCGUCGCUGCUUCAGCCGCCGCCCCCUGCAGCAUCUUCUACGUCGGGACCACAGCCUCCGCCUCCACAAAGCCUGAACCUCCUUUCGCAGGCUCAGCUGCAGGCACAGCCUCUUGCGCCAGGCGGAACUCAAAUGAAAAAGAAAAGUGGCUUCCAGAUAACUAGCGUUACUCCUGCUCAGAUCUCCGCUAGUAUCAGCUCUAACAACAGUAUAGCAGAGGACACUGAGAGCUAUGAUGAUCUGGAUGAAUCUCACACGGAAGAUCUCUCUUCUUCGGAGAUCCUUGAUGUGUCACUUUCCAGGGCUACUGACUUAGGGGAGCCCGAACGCAGCUCCUCAGAAGAGACCCUAAAUAACUUCCAGGAAGCCGAGACACCUGGGGCAGUCUCUCCCAACCAGCCCCACCUUCCUCAGCCUCAUUUGCCUCACCUUCCACAACAGAAUGUUGUGAUCAAUGGGAAUGCUCAUCCACACCACCUCCAUCACCACCAUCAGAUUCAUCAUGGGCACCACCUCCAACAUGGUCACCACCAUCCAUCUCAUGUUGCUGUGGCCAGUGCAUCCAUUACUGGUGGGCCACCCUCAAGCCCAGUAUCUAGAAAACUCUCUACAACUGGAAGCUCUGACAGUAUCACACCAGUUGCACCAACUUCUGCUGUAUCAUCCAGUGGUUCACCUGCAUCUGUAAUGACUAAUAUGCGUGCUCCAAGUACUACAGGUGGAAUAGGUAUAAAUUCUGUUACUGGCACUAGUACAGUAAAUAAUGUUAACAUUACUGCUGUGGGUAGUUUUAAUCCUAAUGUGACAAGCAGCAUGCUUGGUAAUGUUAAUAUAAGUACAAGCAAUAUUCCUAGUGCUGCUGGUGUGAGUGUUGGGCCUGGAGUUACCAGUGGUGUUAAUGUGAAUAUCUUGAGUGGCAUGGGCAAUGGUACUAUUUCUUCCUCUGCUGCUGUUAGCAGUGUUCCUAAUGCAGCUGCAGGGAUGACUGGGGGAUCGGUUUCAAGUCAGCAGCAACAACCAACAGUUAACACUUCGAGGUUCAGAGUUGUGAAGUUAGAUUCUAGUUCUGAGCCCUUUAAAAAAGGUAGAUGGACUUGCACUGAGUUCUAUGAAAAAGAAAAUGCUGUACCUGCUACAGAAGGUGUGCUGAUAAAUAAAGUGGUGGAGACUGUAAAGCAAAAUCCGAUAGAAGUGACUUCUGAAAGGGAGAGCACUAGUGGGAGUUCAGUGAGCAGUAGUGUCAGCACACUGAGUCACUAUACAGAGAGUGUGGGAAGUGGAGAGAUGGGAGCCCCUACUGUGGUGGUGCAGCAGCAGCAGCAGCAACAACAACAACAACAGCAACAACCAGCUCUCCAAGGUGUGACCCUCCAACAGAUGGAUUUUGGUAGCACUGGUCCACAGAGUAUUCCAGCAGUUAGUAUACCACAGAGUAUUUCUCAGUCACAGAUCUCACAAGUACAAUUACAGUCUCAAGAACUGAGCUAUCAGCAAAAGCAAGGUCUUCAGCCAGUACCUCUGCAAGCCACUAUGAGUGCUGCAACUGGUAUCCAGCCAUCGCCUGUAAAUGUGGUUGGUGUAACUUCAGCUUUAGGUCAGCAGCCUUCCAUUUCCAGUUUGGCUCAACCCCAGCUACCAUAUUCUCAGGCGGCUCCUCCAGUGCAAACUCCCCUUCCAGGGGCACCACCACCCCAACAGUUACAGUAUGGACAACAGCAACCAAUGGUUUCUACACAGAUGGCCCCAGGCCAUGUCAAAUCAGUGACUCAAAAUCCUGCUUCAGAGUAUGUACAACAGCAGCCAAUUCUUCAAACAGCAAUGUCCUCCGGACAGCCCAGUUCUGCAGGAGUAGGAGCAGGAACAACAGUGAUUCCUGUGGCUCAGCCACAGGGUAUCCAGCUGCCAGUGCAGCCCACAGCAGUCCCAGCACAACCUGCAGGGGCAUCUGUCCAGCCUGUUGGCCAGGCUCCGGCAGCAGUGUCUGCUGUACCUACUGGCAGUCAGAUUGCAAAUAUUGGUCAGCAAGCAAACAUACCUACUGCAGUGCAGCAGCCCUCUACCCAGGUUCCACCUUCAGUUAUUCAGCAGGGUGCUCCUCCAUCUUCGCAAGUGGUUCCACCUGCUCAAACUGGGAUUAUUCAUCAGGGAGUUCAAACUAGUGCUCCAAGCCUUCCUCAACAAUUGGUUAUUGCAUCCCAAAGUUCCUUGUUAACUGUGCCUCCCCAGCCACAAGGAGUAGAACCAGUAGCUCAAGGAAUUGUUUCACAGCAGUUGCCUGCAGUUAGUUCUUUGCCCUCUGCUAGUAGUAUUUCUGUUACAAGUCAGGUUAGUUCAACUGGUCCUUCUGGAAUGCCUUCUGCCCCAACAAACUUGGUUCCACCACAAAAUAUAGCACAAACCCCUGCUACCCAAAAUGGUAAUUUGGUUCAAAGUGUUAGUCAACCUCCCUUGAUAGCAACUAAUACAAAUUUGCCUUUGGCACAACAGAUACCACUAAGUUCUACCCAGUUCUCCGCACAAUCAUUAGCUCAGGCAAUUGGAAGCCAAAUUGAAGAUGCCAGGCGUGCAGCGGAGCCCUCCUUAGUUGGCUUACCUCAGACUAUCAGUGGUGACAGUGGGGGAAUGUCAGCAGUUUCAGAUGGGAGUAGCAGCAGCCUAGCAGCCUCUGCUUCUCUUUUCCCGUUGAAGGUGCUACCGCUGACGACACCCCUGGUGGAUGGCGAGGAUGAGAGCUUUUGGUACAUUUCCAAACUGGCUGGCAGAGCCAGGAGGAAGUGAAGGCAUUAGAAACACUAACUUUGGUUGGUUGCUACCGUCUUAGUGCUGAGACUAUAACCUUUGUUGGUUGAUUGAUAGAGAACAAGAGAACACAAUCCUCGUUCCACUAACAGGUAAGGAACCCUUGUGAUAACUAGUUGGUAUGAGAGGGAGAUUACUUGAUAGCAUUUCAUAAAAACUUUAUCCCAAAAUAUAACAUGUCCUAGAAAUAGGAUACUGUGACUGACUGUACUCCGUAGAACAAGGAUACGCAGCACCUUUAUAUUUAGAAUAAGAUCUGAAAUUUAAUAGGGAUGUAUUACUCUGUACCACAAAGCAUAAUUGAUCUGUUUUCCAAAGGCAACACUGUUAAAAUUUAUCCUGCAGUCCCUGUAACUUUAAAUAUGUAUCUGCCUAUCUUAUUCUCCUUUCAGCUUUUCCUUGAUCAGAUGCUAUGUGCUUUGAACUUCCUUCUCUUAUUUAUUCCUAUAAUAAAGCUAACUAUUUUCUAGUAUCUUUGCCAUCAUCUAUAAUUUGGGUAUAUCUUACUGCUUUAAUUUCUAUGUUAUAGCCAUUAAUGAUUAUUCCUGGUUCUUCUUGACCCAAAAGAAAAUGAUUAUGCAUUUUAAAAAGGAUUUUGAGUCUGUAUUGCCUAUAUCCACUAUUCUGCCUUCCCAGUUUUAAAGCUGAGUGCUUGAAGAAUAAAUCUUUUCAGUGACAGUAGUCAUAAGCUUUCAUAAAAUAUAGGCUUAGCUUUGUAUUGCUAUAAUAUGGGCCUAUAGUGUGAUUAAUUCUUUAAGUUAAUGAAGACUUGAACUCAGAGAAGAAAUUCAGCUUCUUAGACUUUCCCAAAGUUUAGUAGUAUUCCUGUUAAUAUACUUGGUUUUUUCUGUUUCUACUUUUCAGUCCAUCUUCUUUUCUUUGACAGAAGAAUUAACUGGGACUCCUCCUUUGAUAUAUCUGAGGUUGUGUGCCUUUUCCCUGUCCCUUAAAGACAACUAUGAUCUUGUUUCCAGUCAUAAUUUAUCAUUUUUGAUUUGGUCUUCCACUCAGAGUUGAGUGGUUUAUCACAGAGUGUGUUAUGGCUUAGACCAAUACAGGUCCCUUCUUAAUAGUUACUGAGGAAUUAAUCAUUUGUGGUGACAGACUUCUAAAAUUCAAAUUAAGAAGGCACUAAAGAAAGUAUGCCCAAAGGUAGCUCCUUUUUAUCCUGAGGAUUAAGCCAUUACAAACUCAAAUGACCAGAGAAUGUAAUUUCUUAAUAAGAAUUUUUCCUUAAAUCUAUAUUCAGCUCUCUAUUUCAGUGCUUCUCUCCUACCAGAGGUGCAAGGAGUGAUCCUAGAACCACAGAUACAGCCAAGACCACGGAGAGCUUUUGACGUCAGGGGUCCACUUUCUCCACUGAACCCUUGGAGACAGAAUAUCCAGCUUCUGGAGAGAGUGGGAAAGGAUAAUAAACAAGUGGGUGCUUUCCAUUAUUUACUUGGGUUAAUUUAUAGAUUGGAGUGUCCUUCCAUUGCCCAUUUAAUUCUGUGGUAAACUCCUUGGGUUCAUUUAAGAACCAGGUGGGACUGCAAUCUGUUUUGUUUUUCUGAGAAUGCUAACUAGUACUCAUUCAAAAAUGAGACCUAAAAUUUAAUUUUCUCUCCAGAUAAUUAAAGCAGUGGAUGAUUUGGGGCACAUGAUUUGACGAAUGCCUAUGUAGUCCACAGGAAUUUUAAAACGGGAAUAUCUACCCAUUUUGGCCUUUGUGGUAUUAGUGGACUUCUAAGUGCUCUUUUAUAUUCAAGUAAUUUAAAAGGUUCUGUAUUUCAUCUUUGGGCAAACUGGACAUUUGAAGUCUAAUUUAUACAGUCACAUGUCCAAGUGUUAUCCUACACUGUUAGUGAGAACCUUUUGGUCUUCUUCCUACCUCAAAUGUUAGGACUUCAUAUUAGAUCUUUUAAAAGAUGCAAUGAUAGUACUAUUAUGGUUUUACUGUCAAUUCUAGGCUCCAUUCUUUAAUAAAACAUAAGUAUGAAUGAAUGUAAGUUUCAGGAUACAGUAUCCCUGAAAGCUAUGUUUAAUAUACUCAAAAGUCAUUUUCUAGUCCCUAGGAAUAAAUAUUUAUGGUAAAAGAACCCUUUCCUAGAUUUCCCCCAUGGCAUUAAGAUGGUUUUCUCUUAGUUUCUUUGAUGCCAAGGGUAGGAUUUGAUUCCAGGAAGUUCUUAUCACCUACAAUGGGUAGAAUGUGAACUUGUUACCUUUGGCAAGUUUUCAUUUUUCCUUGGUGGAUUCCUUCUGUGACUCCAGGUAUCUUGAUAAUGGGAGACUGGUUUAUUUGUUCUUUAAUUGCCCAGAUUUCUUUCAACUGGUAAAACAUCAUACUUCUUCAGCAAAAGGAAUUCUUCUAGCAGAGCCUUCAUGGAUGAUAUCUGUCACACAUGCCAGCACCUGCAGUUUGGAAGGCAGUGGUGAAUGGAUCCAUGCAAUAUGUCUAGAAGACACAAGGAUGAGCCAGCCACCUGAUCUUGUCAUUUAUAAACUUUUAAGAAUUACUCUGGUUUACUUUUGGUCUGAAAAUGGAAAGGCCCAAAUAAUGAAAUAAUCUUUUCAGAUUGGAAUUUUACAUGGCCAUGAAAAUAUUUCUUUCUAUUCAGAAGACUGAAAUAGAGGAAGCUUGAGAGACUCCUUUCUUUUAAAAGCGGCUCUCUGUAUCUGUUUCAUUUAAAACAUUUGUGGGAUUGAAAAUCACCUUAAUGAAGUAGGCAAACAUUUUUUUAAGUAGUAGAGGAAGUCCAGAAAACUUAAUGAAAUGGUUUUUUUUGUUGCCUGACACUGAAAGUAACUAGUAAAUAAAGGGUGAACUUCUUAAUUAUUCGAAAACUGCUUUUAAUAUUAGGAUAUACUCUUUUAGCUCAUCUUCGCUGGUCUUGAGGCUUAUUAUAAUUGUCAAAUCAACAAAGUUUCUAAUAGAGAAGUAGAAGAAAUAUCUUUUGAGAUGUAAGUAGCUUGGUCUGUCUUCUAAAGUAAUACAUACCUGUUAAACUUGAGGUAUUUUUUUCAUACUGAAGGCAUUCUAAAGUUUGGUACUGUCACAAAACAGUAGUUUACAGAGCAGAAGCACUUAGUAUUAGAAUAAGCCUGUAGGUGUGAAGGAAUAAGUGUUGCAAAAUAGUUAUUUAUCCAAGCUGUCAAUUAAUUGAUUGAAGUAGUUAUCAAAAUGUUUCUGUUUCUUUCUUUGGUAUCUAUUAACUGGUCAGUCAAAAGCUAUUAAAGAAUGUUUUUAAAGUCACCUAAUGCUGCCAGUUUGUUAAAUUUGGUAUACAUUUUAAGAAUAGACAUUCUAGAGUUAUUAAUAUGGAAGCAGCUAAAAUGUUUUAGGAAAUCUCAAAAGUUUUAGAAGCCACAUUUGCUAAAGCAUAACCUGCACUUAGUCUUUCUUGGCUAUCUGUAUUUUUUUCUCAUUAAUUAUAAAUAAAUUUUUGUUAAGUAUAGUAUUUAAAAGUAAGUUUAAAGGUUCAAUUUGAACUGAAAUUUCCCCAGAGAGCUUUGAAUUCCCAUAAGUGAUUACAGCUUUUACUCCCGACUUGUUUUUAGUAAAUGUUAAUAAGACAAUUGGUUUACAAACACAUAUAAAUUAAAAAAAACAACUGUCCAUCGUUUUAGGAAGAACUGAAGGAACUAAAAAUGAUAUUUGCUUGGAAAUUAAGUUAGUUGAACUCUUUGAACCACAGUAGAAACCGCUUUGUGUGGCCUGUGAGAUUAUAAGCUUUUUGUUUCAGCUUUGAAGAUGAAAAGUGAUUUAAUCUCUUAAUCUCAUGCUUUGAUUGAAUUUUAGCUCUGUUCCUUAAAAUAUGCAAAAGGAAAUGUAAGUGCAUUUCUAGUCACCUCAUGCCACUACAAGCUAUUUAUUUAAAAGUGAAACUUUUUGUAUAUUAUUGUGAACUGAUUUGUUUAUUUAAACUUUUAUUUUGGUGAAUUUACCUUUGAGUUUUUUUAUAUUUUAUGUCACAAAAUGAAGUCCUAUAUUUUUCAGUGUUUAUGAAUAUUAAUAUAAACUAUUUUUUUCUAGAAUGACUAAUUGUGUAAUAUCUGUAUUAUGUGAUAAUUUGAAAUCUAAUAAAUAUUUUCUCCAUGAAAAAAA